GUGAGAGCGGUAAGAUGGCGGCGGCGGCGGUGGUGGAGUUCCAGAGAGCCCAGUCUCUACUCAGCACCGACCGGGAGGCCUCCAUCGACAUCCUCCACUCCAUCGUGAAGCGUGACAUUCAGGAAAACGAUGAAGAGGCAGUGCAAGUCAAAGAGCAGAGCAUCCUGGAACUGGGAUCUCUCCUGGCAAAGACUGGACAAGCUGCAGAGCUUGGAGGACUCCUGAAGUAUGUACGACCCUUCUUGAAUUCCAUCAGCAAGGCUAAAGCAGCUCGCCUGGUCCGAUCUCUUCUUGAUCUGUUUCUUGAUAUGGAAGCAGCUACAGGGCAGGAGGUCGAGCUGUGUUUAGAGUGCAUCGAAUGGGCCAAGUCAGAGAAAAGAACUUUCUUACGCCAAGCUUUGGAGGCAAGACUGGUGUCUUUGUACUUUGAUACCAAGAGGUACCAGGAAGCAUUGCAUUUGGGUUCUCAGCUGCUGCGGGAGUUGAAAAAGAUGGACGACAAAGCUCUUUUGGUGGAAGUACAGCUUUUAGAAAGCAAAACAUACCAUGCCCUGAGCAACCUGCCGAAAGCCCGAGCUGCCUUAACUUCUGCUCGAACCACAGCAAAUGCCAUCUACUGCCCCCCUAAAUUGCAGGCCACCUUGGACAUGCAGUCGGGUAUUAUCCAUGCAGCAGAAGAGAAGGACUGGAAAACUGCGUACUCAUACUUCUAUGAGGCAUUUGAGGGUUAUGACUCCAUCGACAGCCCCAAGGCCAUCACAUCUCUGAAGUACAUGUUGCUGUGCAAAAUCAUGCUCAACACCCCAGAAGAUGUCCAGGCUUUGGUGAGCGGGAAGCUUGCACUUCGGUAUGCAGGGAGGCAGACAGAAGCAUUAAAAUGCGUGGCUCAGGCUAGCAAGAACAGAUCACUGGCAGAUUUUGAAAAGGCUCUGACAGAUUACCGGGCAGAGCUCCGGGAUGACCCAAUCAUCAGCACACACUUGGCCAAGUUGUAUGAUAACUUACUAGAACAGAAUCUGAUCCGAGUCAUUGAGCCUUUUUCCAGAGUACAGAUUGAACACAUAUCUAGUCUCAUCAAACUCUCCAAGGCCGACGUGGAAAGGAAAUUAUCACAGAUGAUUCUUGACAAGAAAUUUCAUGGGAUUUUGGACCAGGGGGAGGGUGUCCUGAUUAUUUUCGAUGAACCCCCAGUAGAUAAAACUUACGAAGCUGCUCUGGAAACAAUUCAGAACAUGAGCAAAGUAGUGGAUUCCCUCUACAACAAAGCCAAGAAACUGACAUAGGUGAGUGCUGGCUUCAGGACCCCAGGGCUGGGCAGCUCUGUCUUCUGCGUGUCGAGACUGAAAACCUCCUCCUGGUGUCCUCAUGGCUUCCUGAUUGACACUGCUCUGUCUUCUCUUGCAGAGUUGGAUCUGUAGCGGUCCUUUGGAGAGUGUGUGUGGCGGGAGAGUGAAACCUUGGGGGAAAAUGCUAGGAGAUUCUUUUUUCUUUUUGUUCUACUUUUCGCUCGGAAAGUUUUUAAAUCCUCAUUUGGUGCAUCUGUAUUCCAGCCAAUAGGUGUGCCAGUUUUCAUGUAAUCUUUACUGGCCCAACUUGGGAGUGGGGAAAUUGCUUAAAAAAAAAGAAAAAGAAAAAAAAAAAGAUUAUUCUAAAUAAAAGGAAAAAGGCUUACACUACCUAAAGCUGUGCUCUCUGCCUCCUGGGAGAGGGCCGCAAAGCCAGGCACCCCGCCAACCACUGGGGGUCCUAAUCCACCUGCUGGGCAUCACCUCUCCUCCUCCUCAGAAUUGGGUGUUUGCUGACCAUCAAAAGCAAUGACUUUUUAUUCUGUUUGUACUGAACCAAAACAAACAACUGUGUAUAGACUGCUGUUUUCUUUUUUAUUUGAAAUGAGGCAUUUUGGUGUUCUUUCCCCUACCAUACGGCCUGUCUGCCCUUCCCUCCCCACAUUGGCUCCAGCAGAGUAGCCGAAGGUCCUGCCGCCGCCGCCACCACCACCACCACUGCAGCAACAACAGCAGCAGCAGCAGCAGCGCCUGCAUAGCUCCACUCUGACCUGUGAAGGAAUGGGGAUGAGGCCAGGAGCUAGUGUCUACCACGGCCACACAGGGAGCAGUGUGGGCCCUUAGCCCCCAAGGGGCCUGCUAUGCAUGUGGCUUUUUUUUUUUUUUUAAACACAGUAAACUAGAUUAGUCGUCAGUGUUUUAAUUGCCCCUCUUCUCCUCUCCUGCAUUCCUCUCCUCUCUUCUUUCCUCUCUGUCCCUUCUCUUUCCCCUCUCAACCAGGAGACCAUCAUGUCUCUCUGCCUUCCUCCUCUCCCCUCCAGGGGAGUCAGGCUGUCUGUGAAAGCCAUGAGCUUCUCUCCCUCUCCCACUCCUCCUCUCCUACUUUCAGAUGGAUUUAUUCCUUUUUUAAACAAUGAACAUCGGAAAUGAGACUGUGGGGUGUGGUUUCUCUCUCUCUUUUUUUUUUAAUUUUCUUUGUUGGGUUUUUGAGCAACCUCAUGUCCCCUUCCCAGGGAGCUUUUUAAUUUACCUCUUAGAACUCAAGUGGAUGGGAAGUAGAGCACUAUGUGUCAGUAUGCUUUGUUUUCUGACACGAUUACACAGCGAGGCUUUAAUGCCAUUUGGGUAGGUGAGCUUCUGCACUUCUGUUGUGCUGAACUGUAUUUUCUUCUCUCAUCUCCUCUUUGUCUUUUUCUCUUUUCCUCUCCUUCCUGCCUUCUUCUGCUGGCCUCCUUUUCUCUUUCUUUACCUUCCUUGGAUUAUCCUUCCAGGUUUUCAUAAUAAAUUUAUAUUUUGUAAAAGGAUUUUGUUGUACCAGGUUUUGCAUCCUCACUGAAUCUGACUGGCUUUUAUUUUCCUCUCCAAAAUCAGGUUUUUGUUCUCAACAUCUUUCCCCAUCAUGUCUAGUCACUGUUUUGGUUUUGGCACCAUCAGUAUCAAAUGUACAAACGGUUCUUGCUAACCAACACCAGGUAUAUCUGAUGUUCAGAUGAGUUCCAAUAAAAAUAAUUUUUUUUUUUUUCAAAAGGUGUCUUUUUCUUGAGUGCUGGAGGGCUUCCAAGCAAGUCCAGACAGCUCUGUGUGGCCCCACACUAGUCUAGCUCUCAUCUGGCCAAAGCUGUUAUCUCAUUUGUGUAAUGGGAGUCCUUAAGGUAAAUUUGGGGUCCAAACUUGGAGGGCUUUGGGGGCAAGAAAGUUGGUGUGUGAGUUCUGAGGUUGGAAAUGAGUUCAGGUGUCUUCUUCCAGGGCAGCAUGGUCCAGUGAGCACAUGUAAGUUUGGGCAGUAGAUCCUCUGAGCCUACUUUCUCUUCUACUCAGUGAGGAUGCUGCUUCCUUGGCAGGUGAUUGUGAUGUGAAGCUUAGUAAGUCAUAGACGUGCAGGUGUCUGGAGAGUCCUGACAUGCAGUUGUGGUUUCGUUUCCUUUUGGAAUCUUCAAAGGCAGCGAUUUUCAUAUUGCCUCACACCCUGGCGGGGGCGGGGGGCUCUGGGACCACUGGGGGACCUGCUAAAUCCUCUUCAGUCUGAGCAGUUCAGCCAUUGUCAGUUUUAGUAUUGUGUCUCUGUAUUUCACUUGCAGAAAGAGCUUUGCUUCUAUAAAGGACUUUAAAAAGUACUCCAAAGAGAUCUAGUUUUGGAGUAGAGGGGAGAUGUUUUCUCAAACUUAGGGCAGUCCUGAGAUGCUCAGGCAGUAGCCCUUUUCUCAGUUCCCUUUGCGGGUCUUGGUCAGAUGAUGCCCUCUAGACCCGUGCUGUCCAAUAUGUAGCCGCUAGCCAUGUGCAGCUGUCAGGCCCUUGCAACGUGGCUGGUUCGAGCUGUGAUACACUGCAAGUGUAAACACAAACCAGACUUCGAAGGCUUAGUAUGAUAACAAAAGAAAAGGAGUGUAAAAUAUGUCAAUAACUUUUUUAUAUAUGUGUUGAAAUAUUUUGGGUAUUGGGUUAAAUAAAAUAUAUUAUUAAAAUUCA